UUUUUUUUUUUUUUUUUUUUUGAUAGGUUCCAGCUCUGCCACCAAGGCUGGAGUGCAGUGUUGUGAUCAUAGCUCACUGCAGCCUCAAAUUCCUGGGCUCAAGUGAUCCUCCUGCCUCAGCCUCCUGAUUAGCUAGGACUACAGGCACAUGCUACCAUGCCUGGUAAUAAAAUUUUUUUAUUUUUUGUAAAUACAGGGUCUUGUUAUGUAUUUUCUGUAAAUGCGGCUGGUCUGGAACUCCUGGCCACAAGCAAUCCUUCUGCGUCAGCCUCCCAAAUCACUGGGAUGACAGGCGUGGGCCACUGUACCUGGCCCUGGCAUGGUUAUUAGUAGCACCCUCUUUUACUCUAAAAAAUGCCCCAGUUUGGAAACAAAUUAUAUUCCAUCCCUCCUCAUUUAUAGGGGACUUUGUAAUUUACUACAUAUUUUCAUAACUAUACCAUGUGGCUGUCGUCACAGCUCUAGAAAAGCAGGCCAGACGGAGAUCAAUAGCCUCAUUUUACAGAUAAGGAAACAGAUCCAGCUAUGAGCAUGGUCUCCCUCUCUCAGUUGGGAAGUGGUGGCAGAGGGUCUCAAACCUCUGUUUCUUCCUACCCAGUUGUGUCCCUAGCACGAAGUUACCCAUGAAUGGAUUGCUGCCUAAUGUGAUUUGAGUGAUACCAAAAGACCUCCUUGCUUAAAAAUGCCUCCCCAUUUGGUGCCUGUUUCUUUUGGCUCCAAUUACUACUAAGUUAUGUUUAUGUACUAAUGGUUAAGUGCUACCAUUUAAUGUAUUGGGUUAUUUACUGAAUUGUUGUCCAAGAAAUAGGCAUUAAUUUGGGAGAUAAUCCAAAAGGAAGAGGAAACAGGUAAGUUUUGGUGGCAGGACUUGAAGAGUCCUAUUAGCAAGACACAUUAUUAGCAAGAUGGGUCUGGAUCAAGUGUUAUAAAAGGGGUCACUGGGCAGCCAGGGGAUGGCAGCAUUUAAGAGAGACUUUGCUCAUUUUAACUGGUUACCAGGGGUUGAUGGUAGAUGGCAGAGUUGUGGCACACUGGUGCCCAGGGAGUGGGUUCCAGUUGGGCCAUUGAGGGAUCCCCUCGGCUUCGGGGAGUCGUUCUGAGUGUGGAUUGAGCAGGGCCUGGGACAGCUAGAGUCCCUGAGCUGGUCUGUCUGUAUGCUGUGACAUGAAGAACUUUUGGGAAGCAUUGCUGUGCAGGACUGUGUUGCCUGGGCCAUUAAGAAUUGAGAUAAGAGAGGCAGGAAGUCUGGGUGUGUGGGCUUGAAACUCUUGGGUAGGGCAGUUCAUCAAAGGGUGCCAGGCAGGCAGCAGCUGGGUUUGGGGAUCUUGGGCACACAUGUUCCAAAGGCAGGACUGCAGGCAGAUUGGGGCUUUUGAGGUAACAAGCCCUGAGAAGAAUAUGGUGCCUCCACCCUCCCCAAUAUGUAACUCAAAAUAAAAAUUCCAAACCAUAAAAUAGAUAUAAGAAAGGCCAAUAAUUUUCUGGCUUUGCCCAUGAUGACUACUUUGGUGCUUUUUUGGAAAUAUCAUAUUUCUUCAGAAAUUAUUUUGAUUCUCAUUUUUGGGUGUCCCUGACAGGCUGGCUACUGAGCAAGUGUUUAGUCUGCUUGGUGGAUCAUCUCUGAGUGGGUAUGAGCUCAUAAACCAAGGAGCCAGAAGACAUUUGGGCUGGAAGGGAACUUGAAGGCUCCCACUCAUUACACCUGGGCUCAGUGUCUCUUAUUUCAGCCCACCUGGCAUCGGUGGCUCAGCUGCCCAGUGGAGCCAGGCGCCCCUUUCCUGCUCUGGCUUCCAGUUUCCCAGUCGGCUGAGCUUAAGAGUGCAUCUGUUGUCUUGAUGACACAUUAUGUGGUAUGUUCGGGAACCCAGCUCAGAUUUCCUGAGGGCAAACAGCAAACCAAAUAAAAAACACCAAACCCUUUUUCUCCUUGCUCAGCAAAGUCCCUUCCCCUCCUCCAGUCCCCAUUCAUCAGGCUGCUGAAGUUAGCACAAUCCUUCCCCACCAGGGUGGUGGGGCAGAAAGGGGAAGUGGUGCCGGAGGCCCCAAGGCAGGAUCUUGCCAUCCCUCUCUUUUGUGAACCCCAUGCCAAAAAGCGGGUGGAAGGGGCGCUGGGUUUAGUUGUUCAUUUUCAGGGUUCCUGUAGAUAAUGUCAGAGCUUUCUUGGAAUGUAUGAAGAGCGGUUUCUGCAGGAAGAAACCGUGUCCCAGCAGAUCAACUCCAUCGAACUUCUGCAGACGCGACCCCUGGCUCUGCCUGAGGUGGUGAAGUCACAGCGGCCCCUGCAGAGGCAGGUCCACCUGAGAGGCCGGCCGGCCUCCCAGCCCACUGUCAUCCGGGGCAUCACCUACUAUAAAGCCAAGGUCUCUGAAGAAGAGAAUGACAUUGAAGAGCAGCAAGAUGAGUUUUUCAGCGGUGACAAUGGAGUGGAUUUGCUGAUUGAAGAUCAGCUCCUGAGACACAACGGCCUGAUGACCAGUGUCACCCGGAGGCCUGCAGCCACCCGUCAGGGACACAGCACUGCUGUGACAAGCGACCUGAACGCUCGGACCGCACCCUGGUCCUCAGCACUGCCACAGCCCUCGACCUCAGAUCCCAGCAUCGCCAACCAUGCCUCAGUGGGACCAACACUCCAAACAACCUCGGUGUCUCCAGAUCCCACAAGGGAGUCAGUCCUGCAGCCUUCUCCUCAGGUACCAGCCACCACUGUGGCCCACACAGCCACCCAGCAACCAGCAGCCCCAGCUCCUCCGGCAGUGUCUCCCAGGGAGGCAUUGAUGGAAGCUAUGCACACAGUCCCAGUGCCUCCCACCACAGUCAGAACAGACUCGCUGGGGAAAGAUGCUCCUGCUGGGUGGGGAACAACCCCUGCCAGCCCCACGCUGAGCCCCGAAGAAGAAGAUGACAUCCGGAAUGUCAUAGGAAGGUGCAAGGACACUCUCUCCACAAUCACGGGGCCGACCACCCAGAACACAUAUGGGCGGAAUGAAGGGGCCUGGAUGAAGGACCCCCUGGCCAAGGAUGAGCGGAUUUACGUAACCAACUAUUACUACGGCAACACCCUGGUAGAGUUCCGGAACCUGGAGAACUUCAAACAAGGUCGCUGGAGCAAUUCCUACAAGCUCCCGUACAGCUGGAUCGGCACAGGCCACGUGGUAUACAAUGGCGCCUUCUACUACAAUCGCGCCUUCACCCGCAACAUCAUCAAGUACGACCUGAAGCAGCGCUACGUGGCUGCCUGGGCCAUGCUGCAUGACGUGGCCUACGAGGAGGCCACCCCCUGGCGAUGGCAGGGCCACUCAGACGUGGACUUUGCUGUGGACGAGAAUGGCCUAUGGCUCAUCUACCCGGCCCUGGACGAUGAGGGCUUCAGCCAGGAGGUCAUUGUCCUGAGCAAGCUCAAUGCCGCGGACCUGAGCACACAGAAGGAGACCACAUGGCGCACGGGGCUCCGGAGGAAUUUCUACGGCAACUGCUUCGUCAUCUGUGGGGUGCUGUAUGCCGUGGAUAGCUACAACCAGCGGAAUGCCAACAUCUCCUACGCUUUCGACACCCACACCAACACACAGAUCGUCCCCAGGCUGCUGUUCGAGAAUGAGUAUUCCUAUACGACCCAGAUAGACUACAACCCCAAGGACCGCCUGCUCUAUGCCUGGGACAAUGGCCACCAGGUCACUUACCAUGUCAUCUUUGCCUACUGACACCCUUGUCCCCACAAGCAGAAGCACAGAGGGGUCACUAGCACCUUGUGUGUAUGUGUGUGCGCGCACGUGUGUGUAGGUGGGUAUGUGUUGUUUAAAAAUAUAUAUUAUUUUGUAUAAUAUUGCAAAUGUAAAAUGACAAUUUGGGUCUAUUUUUUUAUAUGGAUUGUAGAUCAAUCCAUACGUGUAUGUGCUGGUCUCAUCCUCCCCAGUUUAUAUUUUUGUGCAAAUGAACUUCUCCUUUUGACCAGUAACCACCUUCCUUCAAGCCUUCAGCCCCUCCAGCUCCAAGUCUCAGAUCUCGACCAUUGAAAAGGUUUCUUCAUCUGGGUCUUGCAGGAGGCAGGCAACACCAGGAGCAGAAAUGAAAGAGGCAAGAAAGAAGUGCUAUGUGGCGAGAAAAAAAGUUUUAAUGUAUUGGAGAAGUUUUAAAAAACCCAGAAAAACGCUUUUUUUUUUUAAUAAAGAAGAAAUUUAAAAUCA